GCACAGCGCGGGGCCAGGCUGGGUCCAGCAGCGCGAUGGCAGCUCAGCGGCUGGGCAAGCGCGUGCUGAGCAAGCUGCAGUCUCCAUCGCGGGCCCGCGGGCCAGGGGGCAGUCCCGGGGGGCUGCAGAAGCGGCACGCGCGCGUCACCGUCAAGUAUGACCGGCGGGAGCUGCAGCGGCGGCUGGACGUGGAGAAGUGGAUCGACGGGCGCCUGGAGGAGCUGUACCGCGGCAUGGAGGCAGACAUGCCCGAUGAGAUCAACAUUGAUGAAUUGUUGGAGUUAGAGAGUGAAGAGGAGAGAAGCCGGAAAAUCCAGGGACUCCUGAAGUCAUGUGGGAAACCUGUCGAGGACUUCAUCCAGGAGCUGCUGGCAAAGCUUCAAGGCCUCCACAGGCAGCCCGGCCUCCGCCAGCCAAGCCCCUCCCACGACGGCAGCCUCAGCCCCCUCCAGGACCGGGCCCGGACUGCUCACCCCUGACCCUCUUGCACUCUCCCUGCCCCCCGGACGCCGCCCAGCUUGCUUGUGUAUAAGUUGUAUUUAAUGGUUCUGUAACAAUAA